GCACAGCCUGCGGCGCAGCGGAGGCGGACCGCAGUCGAGUCUGCAGAGUGUUGGGUCUGUAGCCAGCAAAUUACUUCAUCAUCUAGAUUAUCCAUUCAGUUGAUCCUAAUUAGCAAGGAUAACAAGGUAACACAAGGCUUACUUAUAUUCACCCAACAAAAGUGUCUCUGUGGAGCCACUUCCCAGUGAACUACAUACUGAGAUAGGGGUUCCUGGAUGAGAAGGACCAAGGACAGAACCGAGAAGAGUUUAGGGGCAGGUUAUGCGAGAUGGAAAUGGCGCAGAUAACGGAGGGAAGGAUUUGAGGGCUCAAACGUAGGCGUCUGUGUUUCGCAAAAGUUGGAGACGUUCUAGGCUGCCUCUCGUUGCCUCCAUCUCGCUCUGCGCGGGUUUUGGAGGACAUUAGCAUUCUUUCUUGUAUCUCCGUUGAUUCCAGAAUCGUCCGCACUAAAGUCCCCUGCAGCGUGACCAUGUCGAGACCCCGGAAGAGGCUGGCUGGGACUUCUGGUUCAGACAAGGGACUAUCAGGAAAACGCACCAAAACUGAGAACUCAGGUGAGGCAUUAGCUAAAGUGGAGGACUCCAACCCUCAGAAGACUUCAGCCACUAAAAACUGUUUGAAGAAUCUAAGCAGCCACUGGCUGAUGAAGUCAGAGCCAGAGAGCCGCCUAGAGAAAGGUGUAGAUGUGAAGUUCAGCAUUGAGGAUCUCAAAGCACAGCCCAAACAGACAACAUGCUGGGAUGGUGUUCGUAACUACCAGGCUCGGAACUUCCUUAGAGCCAUGAAGCUGGGAGAAGAAGCCUUCUUCUACCAUAGCAACUGCAAAGAGCCAGGCAUCGCAGGACUCAUGAAGAUCGUGAAAGAGGCUUACCCAGACCACACACAGUUUGAGAAAAACAAUCCCCAUUAUGACCCAUCUAGCAAAGAGGACAACCCUAAGUGGUCCAUGGUGGAUGUACAGUUUGUUCGGAUGAUGAAACGUUUCAUUCCCCUGGCUGAGCUCAAAUCCUAUCAUCAAGCUCACAAAGCUACUGGUGGCCCCUUAAAAAAUAUGGUUCUCUUCACUCGCCAGAGAUUAUCAAUCCAGCCCCUGACCCAGGAAGAGUUUGAUUUUGUUUUGAGCCUGGAGGAAAAGGAACCAAGUUAACUGAGAUACUGCUGCUGGAAUGGGCGAGACAUUGCUGCAAAGAAGUCAAGCUUUUUUCAGACAAAAGGUGUGAGGGGGCUUGCUUGGUAUGCUUACCUGGGCUUGUGUACCUCAGUGGUUUUUGUGUACUUUUUUCAAUAAAAUAUCAAAGUUGAA